UGCUUAGUUGGAAGAUUUCAAUGAAGAAGAAAAGCUGCCAUAAAAACAGGUGGCCAAAUCGUCUUCAGAGUCCUCCAGUGAGGAAAGUAGCAGUGAGAGCUCCUCUGAGGAAGAGGAGGAGGAAGAUGAGGACGAGGAGGAAGAAGAGAGUGAAAGCUCAGACUCAGAGGAAGAAAGGGCUCAUCGCUUAGCAGAACUACAGGAACAGCUUCGGGCAGUACAUGAACAACUGGCUGCUCUGUCCCAGGGUCCAAUAUCCAAGCCCAAGAGGAAAAGAGAGAAAAAAGAGAAAAAGAAGAAACGGAAGGCAGAGAAGCAUCGAGGCCGAGCUGGGGCCGAUGAAGAUGACAAGGGGCCUAGGGCACCCCGCCCACCUCAACCUAAGAAGUCCAAGAAAGCAAGUGGCAGUGGGGGUGGCAGUGCUGCUUUAGGCCCUUCUGGCUUUGGACCUUCUGGAGGAAGUGGCACCAAACUCCAGGCUGGAGUGCAGUGGCGUGAUCUCGGCUUACUGCAACCUCCACUUCUCGGGUUCAAGCGAUUCUCCUGCCUCAGCCUCCCAAGUAGCCAGGAUUACAGGCUCCCCAAAAAGGCCACAAAGACAGCCCCACCUGCCCUGCCUACAGGUUAUGAUUCAGAGGAGGAGGAAGAGAGCAGGCCCAUGAGUUACGAUGAGAAGCGGCAGCUGAGCCUGGACAUCAACAAAUUACCUGGGGAGAAGCUGGGCCGAGUUGUGCAUAUAAUCCAAGCCAGGGAGCCCUCUUUACGUGAUUCAAACCCAGAAGAGAUUGAGAUUGAUUUUGAAACACUCAAGCCAUCCACACUUAGAGAGCUUGAGCGCUAUGUCCUUUCCUGCCUACGUAAGAAACCCCGGAAGCCCUACACCAUUAAGAAGCCUGUGGGAAAGACAAAGGAGGAACUGGCUUUGGAGAAAAAGCGGGAAUUAGAAAAGCGGUUACAAGAUGUCAGCGGACAGCUCAAUUCUACUAAAAAGCCCCCCAAGAAAGCGAAUGAGAAAACAGAGUCAUCCUCUGCACAGCAAGUAGCAGUGUCACGCCUUAGCGCUUCCAGCUCCAGCUCAGAUUCCAGCUCCUCCUCUUCCUCGUCGUCGUCUUCAGACACCAGUGAUUCAGACUCAGGCUAAGGGGUCAGGCCAGAUGGGGCAGGAAGGCUCCGCAGGACCGGACCCCUAGACCACCCUGCCCCACCUGCCCCUUCCCCCUUUGCUGUGACACUUCUUCAUCUCACCCCCCCCCCGCCCCCCUCUAGGAGAGCUGGCUCUGCAGUGGGGGAGGGAUGCAGGGACAUUUACUGAAGGAGGGACAUGGACAAAACAACAUUGAAUUCCCAGCCCCAUUGGGGAGUGAUCUCUUGGACACAGAGCCCCCAUUCAAAAUGGGGCAGGGCAAGGGUGGGAGUGUGCAAAGCCCUGAUCUGGAGUUACCUGAGGCCAUAGCUGCCCUAUUCACUUCUAAGGGCCCUGUUUUGAGAUUGUUUGUUCUAAUUUAUUUUAAGCUAGGUAAGGCUGGGGGGAGGGUGGGGCCGUGGUCCCCUCAGCCUCCAUGGGGAGGGAAGAAGGGGGAGCUCUUUUUUUACGUUGAUUUUUUUUUUUCUACUCUGUUUUCCCUUUUUCCUUCCGCUCCAUUUGGGGCCCUGGGGGUUUCAGUCAUCUCCCCAUUUGGUCCCCUGGACUGUCUUUGUUGAUUCUAACUUGUAAAUAAAGAAAAUAUUAUUCAAGUUUUGAGUUACCUUAAUAUUUGCUUUUGUAGUGUUUCAAAAGGAACAUCAUAAGAAUUGUCUUGAUAAUUUUGAGGGAAAUAUUACUGCAGUGAGAAAAGGCAAUAGCUAACCUAUAAUUGGAUUGUCUUAAUUUUUAAACCAGUAGGCUUUUGCUGUGUUUUUAAUAAAGUAAAUAUGACUUUUGUAAAUUGA